AUGGGCCUGCUGGCCAGUGCUGGUUUGUUGCUGUUGCUGGUCAUCGGCCACCCCAGAAGCCUAGGACUGAAGUGUGGAAUUCGCAUGGUCAACAUGAAAAGUAAGGAACCUGCCGUGGGAUCUAGAUUCUUCUCUAGAAUUAGUAGUUGGAGAAAUUCAACAGUGACUGGACAUCCAUGGCAGGUCUCCCUAAAAUCAGAUGAGCACCACUUCUGUGGAGGAAGCUUGAUUCAAGAAGAUCGGGUUGUUACAGCAGCACACUGCCUGGACAGCCUCAGUGAGAAGCAGCUGAAGAAUAUAACUGUGACUUCUGGGGAGUACAGCCUCUUUCAGAAGGAUAAGCAAGAACAGAAUAUUCCUGUCUCAAAAAUUAUUACCCAUCCUGAAUACAACAGCCGUGAAUAUAUGAGUCCUGAUAUUGCACUGCUGUAUCUAAAACACAAAGUCAAGUUUGGAAAUGCUGUUCAGCCAAUCUGUCUUCCUGACAGCGAUGAUAAAGUUGAACCAGGAAUUCUUUGCUUAUCCAGUGGAUGGGGCAAGAUUUCCAAAACAUCAGAAUAUUCAAAUGUCCUACAAGAAAUGGAACUUCCCAUCAUGGAUGACAGAGCGUGUAAUACUGUGCUCAAGAGCAUGAACCUCCCUCCCCUGGGAAGGACCAUGCUGUGUGCUGGCUUCCCUGAUUGGGGAAUGGACGCCUGCCAGGGGGACUCUGGAGGACCACUGGUUUGUAGAAGAGGUGGUGGAAUCUGGAUUCUUGCUGGGAUAACUUCCUGGGUAGCUGGUUGUGCUGGAGGUUCAGUUCCCGUAAGAAACAACCAUGUGAAGGCAUCACUUGGCAUUUUCUCCAAAGUGUCUGAGUUGAUGGAUUUUAUCACUCAAAACCUGUUCACAGGUUUGGAUCGGGGCCAACCCCUCUCAAAAGUGGGCUCAAGGUAUAUAACAAAGGCCCUGAGUUCUGUCCAAGAAGUGAAUGGAAGCCAGAGAGGAAAGGAUUGUAAACCUCAGGGGACAGUGUUAUUUGGAGAAAGUGGGAAGAUUUGUUACCCCCAUUCCAAAGGAGACUACUAUUCUCAUAAUUGCUUAUAUGUUUGGAAAAUAAUGGUACCAGAAGAUAAAAUAAUCCUGAUAAAAUUUACAAGUUUAGACAUGGAAAAGCAAGUUGGAUGUGAUCAUGACUAUGUAUCUUUACGAUCAAGCAGUGGAGUGCUUUUUAGUAAGGUCUGUGGAAAAAUAUUGCCUUCACCAUUGCUGGCAGAGACCAGUGAGGCCAUGGUUCCAUUUGUUUCUGAUACAGAAGACAGUGGCAGUGGCUUUGAGCUUACCGUUACUGCUGUACAGAAGUCAGAAGCAGGGUCAGGUUGUGGGAGUCUGGCUAUAUUGGUAGAAGAAGGGACAAAUCACUCUGCCAAGUAUCCUGAUUUGUAUCCCAGUAACACAAGGUGUCAUUGGUUCAUUUGUGCUCCAGAGAAGCACAUUAUAAAGUUGACAUUUGAGGACUUUGCUGUCAAAUUUAGUCCAAACUGUAUUUAUGAUGCUGUUGUGAUUUACGGUGAUUCUGAAGAAAAGCACAAGUUAGCUAAACUUUGUGGAAUGUUGACCAUCACUUCAAUAUUCAGUUCUAGUAACAUGACGGUGAUAUACUUUAAAAGUGAUGGUAAAAAUCGUUUACAAGGCUUCAAGGCCAGAUUUACCAUUUUGCCCUCAGAGUCUUUAAACAAAUUUGAACCAAAGUUACCUCCCCAAAACAAUCCUGUAUCUACCGUAAAAGCUAUUCUGCAUGAUGUCUGUGGCAUCCCUCCAUUUAGUCCCCAGUGGCUUUCCAGAAGAAUCGCAGGAGGGGAAGAAGCCUGCCCCCACUGUUGGCCAUGGCAGGUGGGUCUGAGGUUUCUAGGCGAUUACCAAUGUGGAGGUGCCAUCAUCAACCCAGUGUGGAUUCUGACCGCAGCCCACUGUGUGCAAUUGAAGAAUAAUCCACUCUCCUGGACUAUUAUUGCUGGGGACCAUGACAGAAACCUGAAGGAAUCAACAGAGCAGGUGAGAAGGGCCAAACACAUAAUAGUGCAUGAAGACUUUAACACACUAAGUUAUGACUCUGACAUUGCCCUAAUACAACUAAGCUCUCCUCUGGAGUACAACUCGGUGGUGAGGCCAGUAUGUCUCCCACACAGCGCAGAGCCUCUAUUUUCCUCGGAGAUCUGUGCUGUGACCGGAUGGGGAAGCAUCAGUGCAGAUGGUGGCCUAGCAAGUCGCCUACAGCAGAUUCAAGUGCAUGUGUUAGAAAGAGAGGUCUGUGAACACACUUACUAUUCUGCCCAUCCAGGAGGGAUCACAGAGAAGAUGAUCUGUGCUGGCUUUGCAGCAUCUGGAGAGAAAGAUUUCUGCCAGGGAGACUCUGGUGGGCCACUAGUAUGUAGACAUGAAAAUGGUCCCUUUGUCCUCUAUGGCAUUGUCAGCUGGGGAGCUGGCUGUGUCCAGCCAUGGAAGCCGGGUGUAUUUGCCAGAGUGAUGAUCUUCUUGGACUGGAUCCAAUCAAAAAUCAAUGGUCCUGCUUCACUUCAGACAAAUAAUAAAUGCAAAACCUUAAAACAACAAUUGCCACCACCCACACCUUCACCAGACAGUGCAUCUUGGCCAGGUUGUUGCUCUGAAGCAGAGCUAGAAAAGCCUAGAGGCUUUUUUCCCACACCACGGUAUCUACUGGAUUAUAGAGGAAGACUGGAAUGUUCUUGGGUGCUCAGAGUUUCAGCAAGCAGUAUGGCAAAAUUUACCAUUGAGUAUCUGUCACUCCUGGGGUCUCCUGUGUGUCAAGACUCAGUUCUAAUUAUUUAUGAAGAAAGACACAGUAAGAGAAAGACGGCAGGUGGAUUACAUGGAAGAAGACUUUACUCAAUGACUUUCAUGAGUCCUGGACCGCUGGUGAGGGUGACAUUCCAUGCCCUUGUACGAGGUGCAUUUGGUAUAAGCUAUAUUGUCUUGAAAGUCCUAGGUCCAAAGGACAGUAAAAUAACCAGACUUUCCCAAAGUUCAAACAGAGAGCACUUGGUCCCUUGUGAGGAUGUUCUUCUGACCAAGCCAGAAGGGAUCAUGCAGAUCCCAAGAAAUUCUCACAGAACUACUAUGGGUUGCCAAUGGAGAUUAGUAGCCCCUUUAAAUCACAUCAUUCAGCUUAAUAUUAUUAACUUCCCGAUGAAGCCAACAACUUUUGUCUGUCAUGGUCAUCUGCGUGUUUACGAAGGAUUUGGACCAGGAAAAAAAUUAAUAGCUCAUUUACAUGGCUCCAAGAAAGAGUUUAUCUUGAUAUCCAGUGCUGCUUACCUGACUGUGCAUUUUAAGACUGAUGAGUCUGAGAGAAAGAGGUUUUAAGCUUAUUUUAGAAGAGAUGAUUCAGGAGCAAUCACAGAAGAGCAAUAUUGAGACCCAAUUUCCUAUCAGUGGAGAGUUUUCACUACUAAUCUGGUGCCAGAGGAAGAUGAUAAAAUAAAUUGACUUUACAUGUAUGACUGCUGGAUGGGGAACAACUGAACUUCACAUUUUUCUCUAUUUUUAAUACGAAUAAUGGUGGGAAAAGUCUUUUAAAAUAAUGGAUCUAAAGGUGACUUCCUGGGGAGGAGCCAAGAUGGCCGAAUAGGAACAGCUCCAGUCUACAGCUCCCAGCGUGAGUGACGCAGAAGACGGGUGAUUUCUGCAUUUCCAUCUGAGGGAGAUUCUGGAAGACCACCGCAAUGUGCCCGGCAUGGGAAGUACAAGCUUGUUGACAUUGUGAGCUGAGGCAGCAGUCACUGCCAUCCCACUGCACCACCUUCACAAGAAUUUCUGCCUGCAGGGAUUGGAUCACAUCUGCCACUAGAGGAGAAGUGAGAUCACUGAAAGAGCAGUGUGGUACAACUGUGAUUACAAAUGGGAAAAGAAAUGCAUAACAGUACACCUGAAAAAUGAAUGUCUUUUCAGUGCUGAAAUAUUCAGUGUCACUUCCGCCCAUCAUUAUCAUUGCAGAGGUUGGUGUUGGUGUGUUUGUACAUUCAAUAUUAAACAUUGGUCACAGAAAGUUAAUGUUGUUUCAUGCCUCCUGGGAACUUACAGUUUGAAUCAUUCAAUUCAUAUCUUGCAUACCAUGUGUAUGCUGUAUAUUUUGAAUACCAUUAUAUACAAUUGUACUGUUUUUUUCUACUUUGGCAAACACUGGAAGAUCAGAAGGGCAAUAUUAUUAAAUCCAUAUAAUUCUUAACUUUACUCACAGGGAUACAGGCCAGAAACUGCUGUGAGCACAAAUAGAUAGGAAAGGUCCCUGCCAGUUUCACAAUUGUGAUGAGCAGUGGACAUUUAAGAGAUUAUUUAUCAGGCACGUCAAUUGACCUUAACAUUUUAGGAUAUUUCAUUUGUUUAUAAGGUAUUUAAUUUAUCUGAGACUCAGGUUGUCUCAAUCCCCCUACCCCUCUAAGCUGUAGCCAAGAAUCAGGGAGGAACUGAGGAAGGUCCCUGAGCCAGAAGUCUAGAUGCCAAAGUCUGUCACAGAAAUCUGCAAUAUAAAAUGAAUAGGAGCCUGAGGCAACUUUUUUUUCUUAUUUUACACAUUGCACCAAAAUGUAUCAUUUGGUUUCUAAGAAUGCAGCAUUCCAAAAGGGCGUAUGGUUCAGCUUUAGGUAAACACAUUGAUUAUCAAAUGACACAGCAAUUCAUAAGGAAAUAGAAAAUUUACAUAUAUAUAUUCAAACAACUUUGAAAAGCAUAAUAUUCAGGAUUUCUUUCCUAUAGAACUCAAUAUUGUGAUUAAAUUAUAAAAGUUUGAAUUAUUAAGCUGCCAUUUCUGUAGAUUAAAAAGUUUGAAAAUUAGCUACUUUAUAUGAUUCAGCCUAAUAAUUGUAAUUACAAUAAUACAUCAAGAUGUUAGCUUUAGUACAUCCACAUUAUGAAAAUUUUGCUCUUCAAAAUUAAAGUCAAAAAGCUUAUAUACUUAAAUUAGGAAUCCUUAACUCUCGAACAAAAUGGUAUGUUUCCCAAAUAUUUCUGUCUGUAUUUAAGGCUGGAGGUAACUGAGGCUUCAUUGAAACUGGUUAAUAAUCUUUGUCUAAUGAACCUUGAUUUAAAAGUUGGAAGUCAAAUAUGAGCACAAAAUAUUUCUGUAAUGGUAUUAGAAAAUAAAACUUCCCUCUUUUCUCACUCUCUUUCUCUUUUAACCUCUCUUCCUUUCCUUCAACCUCUUUUCUCUCUCUUCCCCACCUCCUGUUCCCUUUUACAUUCCCCCUCCCUAACCCCAUCUCUCUGGACUUCUUACACUCUUUCAACUUCUCAAUCCAUCUCUCCCUUUUCACCUCUGUUAAUCACUUUUUCUUUCUCAAUCCCUCUACUUUUUUUUCAAUUAACAACCUCCCUCUUCUCCUUUCUUUUCUCCCUCUCCCCAAUCUCUUAUACUCUUCCAAAUUCUCAUCCUCCUUCCCUCUCUCAAUCCUUCUUUCUCAAUGCCCUCCAUCUUUCUCUUUCAACCAACCUCCCUUCCCCUUCCCUUUCCUUUUCUUACCAACCUUUUCUGUCUUUCUCUUUUCCCUCUUUCUCUCAACCCUCUGCCCAACUCCUCUCUUUUUCUCUCAACCUUUCCUUUCCUUUGCAAAUGCUACAAUGAGAAAGUAUUAUAAAUGUCCUAGUAUUUACUAAAAACCCUCACAUGAAUAUUGGUCUAAAGGUUCUGCUUUCAUUAAGUUAUACUUUUGGAUAGGAACACUGAGGAAAAAUGAAAGAUGAGAUUUGCAAUAGGGAUUCUCUAAUUCUCAUGUUAAUCUGUUUUGUACCAUUUUUACUUUGUCUUUUGUGGAUCUCUUCUUUUUAUUAGAUGAUAUUAAAGGGGAUUAAAGUUGUAUUGUAUGAAAUGUCA